GUAUUUUUACUCCAGAGCCAAUGUAGCUAUUCCGAUGCUCUAAGAUCUGCUCUCUGCAAUGCCCAAACUGACCCCAAUUGCCUUUCUCUAGACCCACUUCUCCACCGUGGGAGAAGUGAUGGAAUUCUACUUGGAGAUCGACCCUGUUACCUUGAACCUGAUCAUCCUAGUUGCGAGCUACGUCAUCUUGCUCCUGGUCUUCCUCAUCUCCUGCGUGCUAUACGACUGCCGAGGCAAGGAUCCCAGUAAGGAGUACGCGCCCGAGGCCACUCUCGAGGCCCAGCCCUCCAUCCGGUUGGUGGUGAUGCACCCAAGUGUCGCUGGGCCCCACUGGCCAAAGGGGCCUGGCCUUUCUUUGGGGGAUCCUGCUCCACUAGGAAAGAAAAGCACCAUGGUAUGAGGCUGGCUAAGGGACACUGGGGAGAGACCACUAGACUUUCCAUAGAGACAAACUGCUCCCUAUCGUGGCUCCAAUUCUCUCAGCACAUGUAUCCCGCUUGAUGAAGGAAGUGAGAGCUCUGUCUUACUUGCUGUUUUCUCGUCACCUUCUUUGUGACAAAAGUAACUGUUUAAGAUGGAGUCUCACUCUGUUGCCCAGGCUGGAGCGCAAUGGUGCAAUCUCAGCUCACUGCAACCUCUGCCUACUGGUUCAAGCAAUUCUCCUGCCUCAGCCUCCCGAGUAGCUGGGAUUACAGGUGUCUGAGGAGCUCCACAAAGGUGUCUUAAGAGACACUGCAAAGAAACAAGGUGAUGGAACUGACUGGCCCCAAUAGAAAUUAGACUGACAGCUAAUAAAAAGAAGCUUUUGAAUCUAUAGCUCUUAACAAGCCCCACUGCUCUUUCUGCCUGCUGUGGCUUACUGUCAUGGGAAACCAUCCUUAGGGACAUUUCGUGGCCUCUGGAUGUGGGCAGACAUUAUAACAAACACUGUAAGCCAGGAGUAUGAAAUCAAGGUGUCAGAGGGGCUGUACUCCCUCCGAAGGCUGCAGGAGAAAAUCUAUUGCUUGCCUCUUCUACCUUUUGGUGGUUCCAGGAGUUCCUUGGCUUGUGAUCACAUCACUGAAAUCUUAACCUACCUGGUCAUACUGCUGCCUCUUCUUCUCUCUCAAAACUUCUCCUGCCUCUCUUCAUACUUGUGAUUGCAUUUAGGGUCCAUCUGGGUACUCCAGGAAAAACUCCUACUGUCAAGAUUUAACUUAAUCAUAUCUUAUGUCAUAUAAAGUCAUGUUCAAUAUUUUACAACAUAAAAUAAUAGUCACAGUUUCUGGAGAUAAGGACAUGGGCGUGUCUUUUGGGGGAUCAUCCUUCAAUCCAUUGCAUCUAUCUAUCAGUGAUCACCCCAACCCAAAUAAACCCGCAUAAUAUUUUCAGGUA